CUUUCUGGGCUCGGACCUAGGUCGCGGCGACAUGGCCAAACGUACCAAGAAAGUCGGGAUCGUCGGUAAAUACGGGACCCGCUAUGGGGCCUCCCUCCGGAAAAUGGUGAAGAAAAUUGAAAUCAGCCAGCACGCCAAGUACACUUGCUCUUUCUGUGGCAAAACCAAGAUGAAGAGACGAGCUGUGGGGAUCUGGCACUGUGGUUCCUGCAUGAAGACAGUGGCUGGCGGUGCCUGGACGUACAAUACCACUUCCGCUGUCACGGUAAAGUCCGCCAUCAGAAGACUGAAGGAGUUGAAAGACCAGUAGACGCUCCUCUACUCUUUGAGACAUCACUGGCCUAUAAUAAAUGGGUUAAUUUAUGUAACAAAAUUGCCUUGGCUUGUUAACUUUAUUAGACAUUCUGAUGUUUGCAUUGUGUAAAUACUGUUGUAUUGGAAAAGCAUGCCAAGAUGGAUUAUUGUAAUUCAGUGUCUUUUUUAGUAGUCAAAUGGUAAAAUGCAGCAUAAGAAUAUAAGUCUUCCAAGUUAGAUAUGAGUGUUAGCUUUUUAUAAGUCUGCUCCUGCCAGUUUGACUUUGAGAUACAUUGGAGCCAACUGUAAACUUUAGUUUUUAAAUUACAGUUAGUUUUUUUGUUUGUUUUUGAGGCGGAGUCUCUGUUACCCAGGCUGGAGUGCAGUAUACCAGUCUUGGCCCACUUCAACCUCCACUUCUUAGGUUCAAGCGAUUCUCCUGCCUCAGCCUCCUGAGUAGCUGGGAUUACAGGCACGCACCACCAUACCUGGCUAAUUUUUGUAUUUUGAGUAGAGAUGGAGUUUUCACCACAUUGGCCAGGCUGUUCUUGAACUGACCUCAAGCGAUCCACCUGCCUUGGCCUUCCAGAGUGCUGGGAUUACAGGUGUGAGCCACCACGCCCAGCCUUGCAUUUAAUAUUUUUAUAAUGUGUCUAGGCUGGGUGCGGUGACUCACGCCUGAAAUCCCAGCACUUUGGGUGGCUGAGGCAGGUGGAUUACUUGAGGCCAGGAGAUUGAGACCAGUGUGGCCAACAUAGCAAAAACCCGUCUCGACGAAAAAUACAAAAAAUAGCUUGGUAUGGUGGCACAUGCCUGUAAUCCCAGCUACUUUGGAGGCUCAGGCACAAGAAUCACUUGAACCUACGAGGCGGAGGUUGCAGUGGGCCAGGAUCGUGCCACUGCACUUUAUUUAGCCAGGACAACACUCUGUCUCCAAAAAAAAGUUUCUGAAGGUAAAAGAUAUACUAAAGGAUAUACAUAUACUGCCUCUUCUAUGAUGUUUCAUUUGACCUACACCAUCAGCAUCUUCAGGAAACAGUAUGAAACUAAUUUCACAUUAAAUGUUGCAAACGUCUGCAAUUCUCCAGUUUUUAGUUUGCACGUAAGGAUUCGUAGGAUUGAUUUCAGAUUGACAGAUGGUUGUAGUAACAAAAAAAUGAAUUGCCUUGGAGAAUUCGAGUUAUUUUAGGCCUGCCUUUGACACUUUUAUGCACUUAAUUCACUGCCAAUUUAGUCUAACUCCUCAACCAUCUGUGGUAUGGACUUCUCAGUCCUCCUAAUUGGUAUGUCUUUUAUCUAUCCCAGAGUCAGUAGUCCUUUAAGGAUGCAAAUUUAAUUCGAUAAGAAUGUGGAUUUACUUCAUCUUUAGGACAGAGUAAAAACCUUUAUUUCACUUGGUCUGACCCCUAUCUUCUAUAACUUGUUUUUUUGCUCAUUACUGGCCUUUGCACGGAUGUCUCCCUUCACCUGUACCUCCUGCAUUGCCUCUGGCAGAAACAUCGCUACCCCAGGAGAAUACUUCACUGGGUCAGGCAUUUGCUAGAUCCAUAGCAGUAACUCAUCUGUGGAUCUCAUUUGUGUCACAAAAUGGUACUCCUACUGAUUUUGUAAUGUGAAGCAAGUACUGUGGGUCAGUAGGGGUAGGACCAGGAGUGACAAGUCAGGAUUUUCAGGCUUCAUAGGAAUGACACAGCUCUCCAGGUGAAUCUCCUGGAGAAUUCUCCAUAGGAUCUCCAGGUGAGUGACCAGGAUUUCAUGUAAGCAUAGGGAAUUGAAUGAGCAUUAGAUGGUCUAAUGCUGCGGUUAAGAACACCAACUUAGCCAAACUGCCUAGAUAGUUGGGUGACUUGGGUUAAGUGACUUAACCUCUCUGCUUCAGUUUCCUGUAUAAUUCUUGGUAGUAGAAUGGAGUAUAUGCUGGGUGUUUGGAUUAUUAAUUUGGAGUCUUACAAAGCUGCUAUGUUACAUGAUUAGGCAUGGAAAACUUCGGUUUUUAUAAUCAGUGAAGUACUGCUUUUUGUUUGUUUUCUGAGAGAGUGUCUGUCACCCAGGCUGAAGUGCAGUGGCAUGAUCUCAGUUCACUGCAGCCUCUACCUCCCGGGUUCAAGCAGUUCUCGUGCCUCAGCCUCCGAAGUAGCUGGGAUUACAGGCUUAUGCCACAAAGCUCAGCUAGUUUUUGUAUUUUUUAUUUUUAGUAGAGAUGGGCUUUCGCCAUGUUGACCAGGCUGGUCUCAAACUCCCAGGCUCAACUGAUAACGUCUGCCUUGGCCUCCCAAAGUGCUGGGAUUCUGUAAGCCACCUCACCCAGCCAUGUAUUGCUUUUUUAUGACAGUUAAAAGAGGAAAGGGCGGGGGACAGUUUACAGACCAGUGAAAGUGCUGAGAUAAAUAUUUUUAUACCUAAGGAAAUAGUGAUUUUCCCAAGAUGAUAGGGAGGCAGGUGAUGUAGAUAGGGCUGAAGAUUAGAUUUCUGGCUCCUAUCUGUGAUUUUCUGCUGUACCAGUCUGCCUUCUAUUUUAUGGGCUCAGUAUUCCUUACCUGCCUCUUCCCAUGCUAAAGAUGGCCCACCUUCGUUUUGUUAUUUAAGCAACUUCAUCCCCUGGCUUGUUUUCACAGUGGUUUUCUGAGCCUUUGACUCUAAGUCAUCUAAUUGAACAUUGUGUUGUGAUAUAAAAAGUAAGUUAGGCUUGUGUUUUUCA